CCCCCAGCAGUGAGUCGCAGCCAUGUUCCUGGUUAACUCGUUCUUGAAGGGCGGCGGCGGCGGCGGCGGGGGAGGCGGGGGCCUGGGUGGGGGCCUGGGAAAUGUGCUUGGAGGCCUGAUCAGCGGGGCCGGGGGCGGCGGCGGCGGCGGCGGCGGCGGCGGCGGUGGUGGAGGCGGCGGUGGCGGUGGAACGGCCAUGCGCAUCCUAGGCGGAGUCAUCAGCGCCAUCAGGUAAGGCGGAGACUAUCAGAGGGGCGGGGCCUGGGAAUGGGAGGAGCCUCAGUGAGGCGUGGUCUGGGAGGGGCGUGGUCUAAAAAUAGAAUAGGAUUAACCUGGAGGCUAACCUGGGUACAUGAAUUAGGCCGGGGAGGCCUGGUUUGAGAGUUCUGCUGUAAGGGGGUGGACCCCAGUGAGGCGGAUAUCAGUCAUUGGGGGCGGUGCUUGAUAUGGGAGUAGUCUGAUUGUGUGGGACCAGGACAAUGUGGUCCUGAGGGGACUGAUGUGGAGUUUUGGCGGGUGGGGCUUAUGGGUCUGGGCUCAGCCUGCAUUGGCUAACCUGGAGAUGAACGUUAAAGCGAGGCGGCUGCGCAGUACAACCCGGAGCCCCCGCCCCCACGCACACAUUACUCCAACAUUGAGGCCAACGAGAGUGAGGAGGUCCGGCAGUUCCGGAGACUCUUUGCCCAGCUGGCUGGAGAUGACAUGGAGGUCAGCGCCACAGAACUCAUGAACAUUCUCAAUAAGGUUGUGACACGACACCCUGAUCUGAAGACUGAUGGUUUUGGCAUUGACACAUGUCGCAGCAUGGUGGCCGUGAUGGAUAGCGACACCACAGGCAAGCUGGGCUUUGAGGAAUUCAAGUACUUGUGGAACAACAUCAAAAGGUGGCAGGCCAUAUACAAACAGUUCGACACUGACCGAUCAGGGACCAUUUGCAGUAGUGAACUCCCAGGUGCCUUUGAGGCAGCAGGGUUCCACCUGAAUGAGCAUCUCUAUAACAUGAUCAUCCGACGCUACUCAGAUGAAAGUGGGAACAUGGAUUUUGACAACUUCAUCAGCUGCUUGGUCAGGCUGGACGCCAUGUUCCGUGCCUUCAAAUCUCUUGACAAAGAUGGCACUGGACAAAUCCAGGUGAACAUCCAGGAGUGGCUGCAGCUGACUAUGUAUUCCUGAACUGGAGCCCCAGACCCGCCCCCUCACUGCCUUGCUAUAGGAGUCACCUGGAGCCUCGGUCUCUCCCAGGGCCGAUCCUGUCUGCAGUCACAUCUUUGUGGGGCCUGCUGACCCACAAGCUUUUGUUCUCUCAGUACUUGUUACCCAGCUUCUCAACAUCCAGGGCCCAAUUUGCCCUGCCUGGAGUUCCCCCUGGCUCUAGGACACUCUAACAAGCUCUGUCCACGGGUCUCCCCAUUCCCACCAGGCCCUGCACACACCCACUCCGUAACCUCUCCCCUGUACCUGUGCCAAGCCUAGCACUUGUGAUGCCUCCAUGCCCCGAGGGCCCUCUCUCAGUUCUGGGAGGAUGACUCCAGUCCCUGCACGCCCUGGCACACCCUUCACGGUUGCUACCCAGGCGGCCAAGCUCCAGACCGUGCCAGACCCAGGUGCCCCAGUGCCUUUGUCUAUAUUCUGCUCCCAGCCUGCCAGGCCCAGGAGGAAAUAAACAUGCCCCAGUUGCUGAUCUCUA